GUGUGAGGCUUAUCAACUGCUCAAGUCAGCUCAUCUCUCUGGCUGCUCCGGCAUAUUUGAGAAGGUCUGUUUCCCUGGUCCUUCUGGGUUUCCACCAAUUGGCAAGAAGGGAUCAGCCUGUCCUAGAGAUCACUCCUCUGCCAAAGAUCCCAACAAGACAACAUGGCUCCCAAGAAGCCUGAGCCUAAGAAGGAGGCAGCCAAGCCAGCUCCAGCUCCAGCUCCAGCCCCUGCACCAGCCCCUGCCCCAGCUCCUGAGGCUCCCAAGGAACCUGCCUUUGACCCCAAGAGUGUAAAGAUAGACUUCACUGCCGACCAGAUUGAAGGUGAGUAUGGACAACCCCACCUCUCCGUCUCUAUUGCACUUUCCUGGAGGAGGAGGAGGAGGAGGAAGAAGAGGAGGAGUAGUUGUCCUCAUGAGUUCAAAGAGGCCUUUUCAUUGUUUGACCGGACCCCGACUGGAGAGAUGAAGAUCACCUACGGCCAGUGCGGGGAUGUACUGCGGGCCCUGGGCCAGAACCCUACCAAUGCCGAGGUGCUGCGUGUGCUGGGCAAGCCCAAGCCUGAAGAGAUGAAUGUCAAGAUGCUGGACUUUGAGACGUUCUUGCCCAUCCUGCAGCACAUUUCCCGCAACAAGGAGCAGGGCACCUAUGAGGACUUCGUGGAGGGCCUGCGUGUCUUUGACAAGGAGAGCAAUGGCACGGUCAUGGGUGCUGAGCUUCGGCACGUCCUUGCCACCCUGGGAGAGAAGAUGACUGAGGCUGAAGUGGAGCAGCUGUUAGCUGGGCAAGAGGAUGCCAAUGGCUGCAUCAAUUAUGAAGCCUUUGUCAAGCACAUCAUGUCAGGGUGAAGCAGAGUCUUCCAGGUGCCUGGCCCUUGGCUUUAGCCAUACCAGGGUGAGUUAAAGAGAGGCCCCGGCUGGGUGAGCUGAGAUGGAGUCCUCGACUUAUCACCACACCACUGCCCCAAGGACCUUACAGGCCCUCCCUGUUAAUAAACAGCUCUAACACGGCCAGGCUGGGCUCUGGGAUUCUGA